GACGUCGCAGCAGCAGCCAUCCUGGCAGUGAGGGGUCACAGUCACGGCCACAGGCUCGCCCAUGCACAGAGGCACGUUCUCGAAGGCAGGAAGAGCGUGGGUGUGCAGAGGUGCAGGGAGGGCGGGACAUCCCCAGGGAAGGAGUUGCGUUCAGGAUGGGCAGCUGUGCCAAGUUCCCAGCUGGUAGGAAGACAGGAAUGCAGGUUGAUUGGGAAACAGGAGAGAGGGCGCAGCGGCUGUGGCAGCUGCCUGGGGUGUGAGACAGCAGCAGGUGUGUGUCAGGGAUGUGGGGAAUUUUCUACCAACCUUCUUUUUAAGUUGAGUCAUUUUCUCUCUUGGUCCUUUGCUGCUUUAUUUUUUUUUUUUUUUUGAGACAGCAUCUUGCGCUGUCACCCAGGCAGGAGUGCAGUGGUGUGAUCUUGGCUCACAGCAACCCCCACCUGCUGGGUUCAAGAAAUUCUCCUGCCUCAGCCUCCCAAGUAGCUGGGAUUACAGGCAUGAGCCACCAUGCCUGGGGUUUCACCAUGUUGGCCAGGCUGGUCUUGAACUCCCAAUCUCAGGUGAUCUGCUUCCUUGACCUCCUAAAGUGCUGGGAUUACAGGCAUGAGCCACCAAGCCUGGCAGUCCUUUGCUUCUUUCCUCCCGCCCUCGUCCGCCAGUAGAACCUCAGAAUUUGUGUCACGGCCAUUGACAAAUAUGUCCCGUGCUGUGAGCAUUUUGGAACCGGGACUUGACUCUGUGGCUGAUCUGGAGGCGCUCUGGGCGCAACAUGAGAUUUCGUGCACGAUCAGCCAGCUGUAGCCAGUUUUUCCUGGUGUGCGUGGUCCUGUGAGUGCCUCACCAGGGUCCCUUGGAGAUGGGUGUGACUCAGCUGGUCAGUGAGAAGGUCGGAGGGGCCGAGGGGACCAAGCUGGAUGAUGACUUCAAAGAGAUGGAGAAGAAGGUGGAUGUCACCAGCAAGGCGGUGACAGAAGUGCUGGCCAGGACCAUCGAGUACCUGCAGCCCAACCCAGCCUCGCGGGCUAAGCUGACCAUGCUCAACACGGUGUCCAAGAUCCGGGGCCAGGUGAAGAACCCCGGCUACCCGCAGUCGGAGGGGCUUCUGGGCGAGUGCAUGAUCCGCCACGGGAAGGAGCUGGGCGGCGAGUCCAACUUUGGUGACGCAUUGCUGGAUGCCGGCGAGUCCAUGAAGCGCCUGGCAGAGGUGAAGGACUCCCUGGACAUCGAGGUCAAGCAGAACUUCAUUGACCCCCUCCAGAACCUGUGCGAGAAAGACCUGAAGGAGAUCCAGCACCACCUGAAGAAACUGGAGGGCCGCCGCCUGGACUUUGACUACAAGAAGAAGCGGCAGGGCAAGAUCCCCGAUGAGGAGCUACGCCAGGCGCUGGAGAAGUUCGAGGAGUCCAAGGAGGUGGCAGAAACCAGCAUGCACAACCUCCUGGAGACUGACAUCGAGCAGGUGAGUCAGCUCUCGGCCCUGGUGGAUGCACAGCUGGACUACCACCGGCAGGCCGUGCAGAUCCUGGACGAGCUGGCGGAGAAGCUCAAGCGCAGGAUGCGGGAAGCUUCCUCACGCCCUAAGCGGGAGUAUAAGCCCAAGCCCCGGGAGCCCUUUGACCUUGGAGAGCCUGAGCAGUCCAACGGGGGCUUCCCCUGCACCACAGCCCCCAAGAUCGCAGCUUCAUCGUCUUUCCGAUCUUCCGACAAGCCCAUCCGGACCCCUAGCCGGAGCAUGCCGCCCCUGGACCAGCCGAGCUGCAAGGCGCUGUACGACUUCGAGCCCGAGAACGACGGGGAGCUGGGCUUCCAUGAGGGCGACGUCAUCACGCUGACCAACCAGAUCGAUGAGAACUGGUACGAGGGCAUGCUGGACGGCCAGUCGGGCUUCUUCCCGCUCAGCUACGUGGAGGUGCUUGUGCCCCUGCCGCAGUGACUCACCCGUGUCCCCGCCCCGCCCCUCCGUCCACACUGGCCGGCACCCCCUGCUGGGUCUCCUGCAUUCCACGGAGCCCCUGCUGCCAGGGCGGUGUCUGAGCCUGCCGGCGCCACCUGGGCCCCGGCCCUUGAGGUACUCCCUGAGCAGGACCCCACACUUGGGUGGGGGGGCUUAUCUGGGUGGGUGGGGAUGCCUGUUUACACUAGCGCUGACUCCCAACGGUGACGGCUCCCUUCCCCACUCCAUGGCGCCAGCCUCCUCCCCCGCUCCCCAACUUCUCGCCCAGCUGGCCGAGGCGGGGCAACACUAAGGUGCUCUUAGAAACACUAAUGUUCCUCUGGGGCAGCCCCCACCUCCGUCCUGACCCGACGGGGGCCCGGCCCACUGCCUACCCUCGAGUCCCGCAGCCUUAACAGGAUGGGAUCGAGGGUCCCCAUGGGGUGGCUCAGAGAUAGGACCCUGGUUUUAAAUCCCUCCCAGCCUGGUGCUGGUGAUGGGCCCUGGCCCUACUCCAGGGCCAAUGCACCCCCGCCUCACACACGCACUCCUUCUCCUCAAGGCCAGGGCAGAGGGCCUCACCGCCUCCCGGGCCUGCUGUCAGCUUGCAGCCCGGGGACAGAGGCCAGCUGGGAUCUGCCUGAGGACAGAGAACAUGGUCUCCUGCAGGGCCCUGCCUCCCAAGCCCCGCCCUCAGAAAGCCAAGUACCUUUUCAGCUUUUUAACUGCCCCCAUCCCAACCCAGGGAGGCCUGUGUCACUCUGGCACAAGCUGCCACCACCAGCCACCCACACCCACCCCAGCACACCUCACACGGGACCACAGCCGCGCUGCCGAGGGCCAAGCACAAAGGUUCCAGUGAGCGCAUGUCCCAGCCCCUGGUGGCCAGGCUCCCCUUGCUGAGCCGCUGCCACUUCACCCUGUGGGAAGUGGCCCCAGCCAUCUCCUCUAGACCAAGGCAGGCAGCCCCGACAUCUGCUUCCUCUAUCGCCCAAUGCAAAAUCGAUGAAAUGGGGAGUUCUCUGGGCCAGGCCACAUUCACAUUCCCCUCCCCCUGUGGUCCAGUGAAGCCUCCGGACCCCAGGCUCUGCUCUGCCCUGCCCUGCACCCCCCUCGUCAGAAGUACAUGAGGGGCGCAGAGAUGAGCACACAGCUUUGGGCACGGUCCAGGGCAAACUGAAAUGUACGCCUGAAUUUUGUAAACAGAAGUAUUAAAUGUCUCUUUCUACA